CUUCUGUUGGGCGUUUCUGCGGAGAGGCGGGAGGCGCUGAGAGUCUGCGCGGAGGUCCGUGCACAGACUGCUUUGCCUGUUGUUGCUCUUCGGAGGCGGCGAUCCCCGAAGGCGAGCUGAAAUACGGCUGCAGGCUACAAUUUGCAGCCGACGAUUAAGGAAGACGACGAGCGGGAGAGGUGGCCCACCCUCAUGGAGCGCUUGUGCUCGGAUGGCUUCGCAUUUCCCCAUUACUACAUUAAACCGUAUCAUCUGAAGAGGAUCCACAGAGCUGUCUUACGUGGUAAUCUGGAGAAACUGAAGUACCUUCUGCUCACGUAUUAUGACGCCAAUAAGAGAGACAGGAAGGAAAGGACUGCCCUACAUUUGGCCUGUGCCACUGGCCAACCGGAAAUGGUACAUCUCCUGGUGUCCAGAAGAUGUGAGCUUAACCUCUGCGACCGUGAAGACAGGACACCUCUGAUCAAGGCUGUACAACUGAGGCAGGAGGCUUGUGCAACUCUUCUGCUGCAAAAUGGCGCCGAUCCAAAUAUUACGGAUGUCUUUGGAAGGACUGCUCUGCACUACGCUGUGUAUAAUGAAGAUACAUCCAUGAUAGAAAAACUUCUUUCACAUGGUACAAAUAUUGAAGAAUGCAGCAAGAAUGAAUAUCAGCCACUGUUACUUGCUGUGAGUCGAAGAAAAGUGAAAAUGGUGGAAUUUUUAUUAAAGAAAAAAGCAAAUGUAAAUGCCAUUGAUUAUCUUGGCAGAUCAGCCCUCAUACUUGCUGUUACUCUUGGAGAAAAAGAUAUAGUCAUUCUUCUUCUGCAGCACAAUAUUGAUGUGUUUUCUCGAGAUGUGUAUGGAAAGCUUGCAGAAGAUUAUGCCAGUGAGGCUGAGAAUAGAGUCAUUUUUGAUCUAAUUUAUGAAUACAAAAGAAAGAGAUAUGAAGAUCUUCCUAUAAAUAGCAAUCCAGUGUCUCCUCAGAAACAACGAGCUGAGAAGGCUACAAGUGACGACAAAGAUUCUGUUUCAAAUAUAGCCACAGAAAUAAAGGAGGGACCUAUAUCUGGGACAGUGUCUUCUCAGAAACAACCAGCUGAGAAGGCUACAAGUGACGAGAAAGAUUCUGUUUCAAAUAUAGCCACAGAAAUAAAGGAGGGACAACAAUCUGGGACAGUGUCUCCUCAGAAACAAUCGGCCCAGAAGGUUAUAUUUAAAAAGAAAGUUUCUCUUUUGAAUAUUGCCACAAGAAUAAUGGGCGGUGGGAAAUCUGGAACAGUGUCUUCUCAGAAACAACCAGCCUCAAAGACUGCAAGUGACAAGACAGAUUCUGCUUUGAAUACAGCUACAGAAAUAAAGGAUGGACUACAAUGUGGGACAGUGUCUUCUCAGAAACAACAAGCCUUGAAGGCUACAACUGACGAGGAAGGUUCUGUUUCUAAUAUAGCCACAGAAAUAAAGGAUGGAGAAAAAUCUGGGACAGUGUCUUCUCAGAAAAAACCAGCCUUGAAGGCCACAAGUGAUGAGAAAGAUUCUUUUUCGAAUAUAACCAGAGAAAAAAAGGAUGGAGAAAUAUCUAGGACAGUGUCUUCUCAGAAACCACCAGCCUUGAAGGCUACAAGUGUCAAGGAAGAUUCUGUUUUGAAUAUAGCCAGAGAAAAAAAGGAUGGAGAAAAAUCUAGGACAGUGUCUUUUGAGCAACCACCAGGCUUGAAGGCUACAAGAGACGAGAAAGAUUCUCUUUUGAAUAUAGCCAGAGGAAAAAAAGAUGGAGAAAAAACUAGGAGAGUGUCUUCUCAUAAACAACCAUCCUUGAAGGCUACAAGUGACAAGGAAGAUUCUGUUCCGAAUAUGGCCACAGAAACAAAGGAUGAACAAAUAUCUGGGACAGUGUCUUGUCAGAAACAACCAGCCUUGAAGGCUACAAGUGACAAGAAAGAUUCUGUUUCGAAUAUACCCACAGAAAUAAAGGAUGGACAACAAUCUGGAACAGUGUCUUCUCAGAAACAACCGGCCUGGAAGGCUACAAGUGUCAAGAAAGAUUCUGUUUCGAAUAUAGCCACAGAAAUAAAGGAUGGACAAAUACGUGGGACAGUGUCUUCUCAGAGACGACCAGCCUUGAAGACUACAGGUGAUGAGAAAGAUUCUGUUUCGAAUAUAGCCAGAGAAAUAAAGGAUGGAGAAAAAUCUGGGACAGUGUCUCCUCAGAAACAAUCGGCCCAGAAGGUUAUAUUUAAAAAGAAAGUUUCUCUUUUGAAUAUUGCCACAAGAAUAACGGGCGGUGGGAAAUCUGGAACAGAGUAUCCUGAGAAUCUGCGCACCUUGAAGGCUACAAUUGAAAAUAAAGAUUCUGUUCUGAAUACAGCCACCAAAAUGAAGGAGGUACAAACAUCCACACCAGCAGAACAAGACUUAGAAAUGGCAUCAGAGGGAGAGCAAAAGAGGCUUGAAGAAUAUGAAAAUAACCAGCCACAGGUGAAAAACCAAAUACAUUCUAGGGAUGACCUUGAUGACAUAAUUCAGUCAUCUCAAACAGUCUCAGAGGACGGUGACUCGCUUUGCUGUAAUUGUAAGAAUGUCAUAUUACUCAUUGAUCAACAUGAAAUGAAGUGUAAAGAUUGUGUUCACCUAUUGAAAAUUAAAAAUACAUUUUGUUUAUGGAAAAGAUUAAUAAAACUUAAAGAUAACCACUGUGAGCAACUUAGAGUAAAAAUUCGAAAACUGAAAAAUAAGGCUAGUGUACUACAAAAGAGAAUAUCUGAAAAAGAAGAAAUAAAAUCGCAGUUAAAGCAUGAAAUACUUGAAUUGGAAAAAGAACUCUGUAGUUUGAGAUUUGCCAUACAGCAAGAAAAAAAGAAAAGAAGAAAUGUUGAAGAGUUGCACCAAAAAGUUAGGGAAAAGUUAAGAAUAACAGAAGAGCAAUAUAGGAUAGAAGCUGAUGUGACAAAACCAAUUAAACCGGCUCUCAAAUCAGCAGAGGUGGAAUUGAAGACAGGAGGAAAUAAUUCAAAUCAGGUUUCUGAAACUGAUGAAAAAGAAGACCUGCUGCAUGAAAACCGCUUGAUGCAAGAUGAAAUUGCCAGGCUCAGGCUGGAAAAAGACACAAUAAAAAACCAAAACCUGGAAAAGAAAUACUUAAAAGACUUUGAAAUUGUGAAAAGAAAGCAUGAAGACCUUCAAAAGGCUCUAAAACGGAAUGGGGAAACAUUAGCAAAAACGAUAGCCUGUUAUAGUGGACAGCUUGCUGCUCUGACAGAUGAAAACACAACGCUCCGUUCCAAACUGGAGAAGCAAAGAGAGAGCAGGCAAAGACUGGAAACAGAAAUGCAAUCAUACCGUUGUAGACUGAAUGCUGCUCGAUGUGAUCAUGAUCAAAGUCACUCAUCAAAAAGAGACCAAGAGCUUGCUUUCCAGGGCACAGUAGAUAAAUGUCGUCACUUACAGGAAAAUUUGAAUUCUCAUGUUCUGAUUCUUUCUCUGCAACUUUCUAAAGCUGAGAGUAAGUCCAGAGUCCUCAAAACUGAGCUCCAUUACACAGGAGAGGCUCUGAAAGAAAAGGCUUUGGUUUUUGAACACGUGCAAAGUGAGCUAAAGCAAAAACAGAGUCAAAUGAAGGACAUUGAAAAAAUGUACAAAAGUGGAUACAAUACAAUGGAAAAAUGCAUAGAAAAACAGGAAAGAUUUUGUCAACUAAAAAAACAAAAUAUGUUGCUUCAACAGCAACUGGAUGAUGCUCGCAACAAAGCUGACAAUCAAGAAAAAGCAAUACUUAAUAUUCAAGCCAGAUGUGAUGCUAGAGUACAAAACCUUCAAGCUGAGUGCAGAAAGCACCGUCUUUUACUAGAAGAAGACAAUAAAAUGUUGGUCAAUGAACUGAAUCAUUCGAAAGAAAAAGAAUGCCAAUAUGAAAAAGAGAAAGCAGAAAGAGAAGUAGCUGUGAGACAGCUUCAACAAAAACGAGAUGAUGUCUUAAACAAAGGAUCAGCAACAAAAGCUCUGCUGGAUGCUUCAUCGCGUCACUGCACCUAUUUAGAAAAUGGGAUGCAGGAUUCAAGGAAGAAAUUAGACCAGAUGAGAAGUCAAUUUCAAGAAAUACAGGAUCAACUUACAGCUACUAUAAGAUGUACUAAGGAGAUGGAAGGCGACACACAAAAGCUUGAAGUAGAACAUGUGAUGAUGAGAAAAAUUAUUAAAAAACAGGAUGACCAAAUUGAGCGGCUUGAGAAAAUCCUGCAGCAUUCAAGUUUGAUGCUGCAGGUGUUUGAGAGCUAGAUGAAGCAUCCAGCCAAACUAGACUACAUGGAGCUCCACAGUGAUCGUCUUCACCUCCAGCUGUUUGCAUUUACUUCUUCCCUCUAUCCUACAUGUGUUUUCCUUCCCCUUCAGAUAUCAACCUAUGAAUUGCCUCUACCAAAAAGCCUACAAUAUUGACACAAACCUGGGCUAGUAUCCCUUCUAUGUCUUCCAAUAAGUGCUGUCUUAUGCUUGUCAUUGUAUGUAUGACUCUGUAUGGGAAUUGCCUGUUUGUUUUUUCAGAUUAUAGCAUACAGUUGUUGAGGGGCGGACCGUAUCAUCUUUAUCUUGUAAUUCCAGUGCUUGUCCUAGUACCUUAGCACAUGGUUGCUGAAUACAUGAACGAAGAGUGAGAAACCAGAAGCUCUGAUACUUAACUGCCAUGAUAAUGAAUUCGGUGUGCAACUAUGGGCAAAUUAUAUUUAAUAGUAAUUGCAUAUUGUACAUAUUUUUCAUUCUUAUUAACACUGAUAAGCUUUUCAGCAUAUACUGACUUUCUCUUAGUUAACUGUGAAAUCAUUUAGAUAAAGAAUAUAAUUCUUUUUCAUUCUAACUUCUGAAUUUAAAUCUGAAUCCUCUAUAGCAGGGGUCCCCAACUCCCAGGCCACACACAGUUCCAUGACCUGUUAGGAAGCAGGCUGCACAGCAGGAGGUGAGUGGCAGGCAAGCGAGUGAAGCUUCAUCUGUAUUUCCAGCCACUCCCUGUUGCUCACAUUAUCACCUGAGCUCUGCCUCCUGUCAGAUCAGCAAAGCCAUUAGAUUCUCACAGGAGUGAAAAUCCUACUGUGAACUGCUCGUUCAAGGGAUCUAGGUCACAUGCUCCUUAUGAGACUCUAAUGCCUGAUGAUAUGUCAUUGUCUCCUAUCUCUUCACGAUGGGACCAUCUAGUUACAGAAAAACAAGCUCAGGACUCCCAUUGAUUCUCCAUUAUGAUGAGUUGUGUAAUUAUUUCAUUAUGUAUUACAAUGUAGUCAUAAUAGGAAUAAAGUGCACAAUAGAUGUAAUACGCUUGAAUCACCAUCCUGAAACCAUCCCCCAAACCCCCAUCUGUGGAAAAAUUAUCUUUCACAAAACUGCUGCCUGGUGCCAAAAAGGCUGGGGACUGCUGCUCUAUAGCUUCUGCACUAGAAUCUACUAAUGAGUAAAAUUUAAAUCAAUAACUAGUUUUAAAAGCAUAACAAGAAUAUGUGCUGUCUGGCUGCAGUGGCUCAUGCCUGUAUUCUCAGCACUUUGGGAGGCCAGUGCAGGUGGAUCACUUGAGGUCAGGAGUUCAAGACCAGCCUGGCCAAUAUGGUGAAAUCCUGUCUCUACUAAAAAUACAAAAAUUAGCUGGGUGUGGUGGUGCAUGCCUGUAGUCUCAGCUACUCGGGAGGCUGAGGUGGGAGAAUCACUUGAACCCGGGAGGCAGAGGUUUCAGUGAGCCAAGAUCGUGCCACUGCACUCCAGCCUGAGCAACAGAGUGACUCCAUCUCAAAUGCAAAACAAAACAGAAAGAAUACAUGCUGACGAAAAAAAUCUAAGACAAUAAAAUUGUAUUACUAGGCUGUUAACAUGAUAUUUUGUUUCCCGUUAAAUGUGUGACAUGCAAAAGUAUUUAUUAAAUGAAAAUAUUUUUUAUCUUUU